GCUUUCGGCUUGCUCGGCGGAGCAAGAUGGCGGACAUCUCCCUGGACGAACUCAUCAGGAAGCGCGGGGCGGCGGCGAAAGGACGGCUUAAUGCCAGACCGGGAGUUGGAGGUGUCCGAUCUCGAGUUGGGAUCCAGCAAGGCCUUCUCAGCCAGUCAACACGCACAGCCACCUUCCAGCAGAGAUUUGAUGCCCGGCAGAAGAUUGGCCUCUCAGAUGCCCGGCUCAAACUGGGAGUCAAGGAUGCCCGGGAGAAGCUUUUGCAGAAAGAUGCCCGAUUUCGAAUCAAAGGGAAAGUGCAGGAUGCCAGAGAGAUGUUGAACUCUCGCAAGCAGCAGACCACGGUGCCCCAGAAGCCCCGCCAGGUUGCUGAUGCCCGGGAGAAGAUCAGCUUGAAGAGGAGUUCCCCUGCUGCCUUCAUAAACCCACCCAUUGGGACAGUGACCCCUGCUCUGAAGCUCACCAAAACCAUCCAGAGAAUGCAUGUGGACCCUGUGGGGUGGAUUCUGACCACUGAGUGUUUCCAGGUUCCACAGCAGAAAGCCAUGGCACCACUUCAUCCCCAUCCUGCCGGAAUGAGAAUCAAUGUUGUCAAUAACCACCAGGCCAAACAGAAUUUAUAUGACCUGGAUGAAGAUGAUGAUGGUAUAGCUUCCGUUCCUACUAAACAGAUGAAGUUUGCAGCCUCAGGCGGCUUUCUCCACCACAUGGCUGGGCUAAGCAGUUCCAAGCUUUCCAUGUCCAAGGCCCUCCCUCUCACCAAAGUGGUUCAGAAUGAUGCAUACACAGCUCCUGCUCUCCCUUCCUCUAUUCGAACAAAAGCCUUGACCAACAUGUCCCGGACACUGGUGAACAAGGAAGAACCCCCCAAAGAGCUGCCAGCUGCUGAGCCUGUUCUCAGCCCAUUGGAAGGCACCAAGAUGACUGUGAAUAAUCUGCACCCUCGAGUCACUGAGGAGGACAUUGUUGAGCUUUUCUGUGUGUGUGGGGCCCUCAAGCGAGCUCGACUGGUCCAUCCUGGGGUAGCGGAGGUGGUGUUUGUGAAAAAGGACGAUGCCAUCACCGCAUAUAAGAAGUACAACAACCGGUGUCUGGACGGGCAGCCGAUGAAGUGCAACCUUCACAUGAAUGGGAAUGUUAUCACCUCAGACCAGCCCAUCCUGCUGCGGCUGAGUGACAGCCCAUCAAUGAAAAAGGAGAGCGAGCUGCCUCGCAGGGUGAACUCUGCCUCCUCCUCCAACCCCCCUGCCGAAGUGGACCCUGACACCAUCCUGAAGGCACUCUUCAAGUCCUCAGGGGCCUCUGUGACCACGCAGCCCACAGAAUUCAAAAUCAAGCUUUGAGCAGGGGAGUGAGGCAGCCAGAAGUGGGGGCAGAGGAGGGUGGCUCUGUUUCCCCAAGGCAAAGCUUAUGACCAAUGGGCCAUCGGACUGGAGACCCCUGAUUGUGGGAAGGGUUGCCAGGGAUAAAGAGCUUCCUCACUGGAUGGGACCCGCCUUUCUGUGUUGUGUUCUGCCCUGUGCUCUUCUCUCUACGUUAACGUUUCCUGUAGUAUGUUUCUUCAUCUCAUCGCCAAGGUAGGCUUGUGUUUUUCAGUGUGUGCCUCCCCGAGCCUCAGCCCCAAGCUGAUUUCUUAUCUGGAAAUGGUACACUGAAUUCUCUGGGUGGCUUUCUUGUGGCCCCAUGGGAUGCAGCGUGGGGGCUGUCUGAAGGACCCUGCUUUUUCCAGGGGCCGAGGGGCUGCCUUUCCUUUGUGUGUAUUAAGCUUUUCAAACAAUGGAGGGGAUGGAGAGCCCUGGUGUCCUGACGGGAGCCAGGUCGGCCUGAGAGCUGUGCCGCUCCUCUGUCUUGUCAGUGGAGGUGCCUGGGUGGGGAGCAGGUCUCAGGCCUCUUGUCCUCUCCCCAGUGGCUCCAGGCCUCACUAGUGGCAAGGGCAGGAUGAGGCUGCACCGCUGGGAAGAGUCUAUCUAAGCUCUUGGCUUGGAGUCCCGUGUCGUCUCCACCCAGAGGAAGUUCUCCAGAGUUCACCUUUCCCUUUUCCUUGAGUUGUGCUGAAUGCCCCACCCCAGCUCUCUUUCCCUUCUGGGUGUCUUUGCUGGGAGGGGGCUGUGUUGUGAGCCCUCCCGGUUCUCACCUCGCCUGGCACUUAACCACACCCUGGUUUUGUGUAGCCGCCAGCUCUCUUCUGGUUGGGCCUUUGAAAGGCUCAGCCUCCCAUUGUGCAGUGCUUGGGUUUGGAGCUUAUUUGAAUGGAAGAGGUCAGUUUGUUCCUGGCUCUCCAUUUCUGGCCUCAGUUGUCUACAGGACAGUGGUCAGGGAUGCCUGGAGGCAUAUAUCCAGCUGCCACCAAGGGGCACUGUUUGUUCCCACUUAUGUGAGUGACCCCAUCCAUCCAUGACCAGAGGAUUAUUUUCCUGCCUUGGCAGAGGAGGAGGAGUCAAGGGAGCAGGGCAGCUCUACCAGGCAAGGUGUUUCCCCAGCAUAGGCGCAGACAGUUGGGACGAAACUUCAGAGCCCAGGCAGUCCCUGAAUGACCAGGCCAGUGUUGUCACUGAGUGGUCCCCUGCUGGUUGGGAGUGAAGAGAAUCCAGGCUGGCAGAGCUGGAGCCAGUUGGGGAGCACGGUUCUGGGAGCUCUGCAAAAUCAGUAGCAAGUGCUGGAAAAGGCACAUGCCGAAGAUACUCAAGAGCUCCCAAGAUUUGCUUGAGGCUAGCCCAGUGAAAAAAACCAGAGACUCAUGUUUCCAGGGGUCAGUCUGUCAGGCAGGAAGGACCCAGGAUUUGAACCCAGCUUCAGUGUGCAGGCUCUGAGGCUGCCCAGGACGGGAAAGUCCAAGGAAGGGGCCUGGUGGUGCUCCACUUGCAGUUCUUUAAAGAAUGCUGCUUUUUAUUCUCCUAACCCUUUCAAGUGGGUGCAGACUUCUCGUUAGCAGCUGGAAGACAUUCCUCCCACACUUUUCCCUUCCUGGCCCAAGAGAGCAUCCAGAAGGCAGUAGGACCUGGUUUUUCAGGUACUGGGAGCCGGGGGCUCACUGCUUGCACUGUGCUUAGGGUAGGGAUGGUAAAUAUCCUCCCUGCAUGGCUUUAUCCUCCCUCUCAUCCCAAAGCAGGUAUCUUCUGGUUGUCACAGAGUUUCAUUGAGUCCAGCUGCAGCCACGUGGCCAUCUGGAGCUGGUGCUAUAGGUGACCAUCUGGUACAUUGAGGGGACCUGUUUGCCUCCUCCACUCUAUAAGCAGUCAUCUUGGGAGACCGGGAGGAGAAGGUGGUGGGCUAGUCCUGUGUCCUCCUCCACUUCCCAUGCCUCUAUGUUACCCAUCUGUGUCUCCUGUGCAGAAGGAGAGGAAGGGGCAUUAAGAGAUGAAGGGUGAUUAUGUAUUACUUAUCCAUUUCUGAAUAAACAUUUGUUAUUCCUA